GAGCCCGGACGCCGCCGCCCACCAGUCAGCCGGCGUCCCCAUGGCCCGGUCCGCGACACUGGCGGCCGCCGCCCUGGCGCUGUGCCUGCUGCUGGCGCCGCCUGGCCUCGCGUGGUACAAGCCAGCGGCGGGGCACAGCUCCUACUCGGUGGGCCGCGCCGCGGGGCUGCUGUCCGGCCUCCGCAGGUCCCCGUACGCGCGGCGCUCCCAGCCCUACAGAGGGGCGGAACCCCCGGGCGGGGCCGGCGCCUCCCCGGAGCUGCAACUGCACCCCAGGCUGCGGAGCCUCGCUGUGUGCGUCCAGGACGUCGCCCCAAACCUGCAGAGGUGCGAGCGGCUCCCCGACGGCCGCGGGACCUACCAGUGCAAGGCGAACGUCUUCCUGUCCCUGCGCGCAGCCGACUGCCUCGCCGCCUGAGCCCGGACCUCUCCUGGCACCGCUGGGGGCCCCCCGCCCCCACCGUCCCACUCGGUGACCCCAGGCCCCUCCGGCGCGGGAUGGCGCCCCAGGUCUCCCCUACUCCGCUCACCCCGCAGUUAAUGGCAAACGAAUAAAUAAAUGAGGCGGCCUCGGA